CCUAGAGAUCCUGGCCUACCCCUCCGCCAAAGCGCGCACUGAGUGCAAACCCCAGAGUCAAUCCCUGUCCCGGCUCCGCCCCCCGCGUCCGAAUCCCGCCCAGCCGGGCCCUCAAGCCCAGUCGGGACUCGAGCCUAGGGAGGCGAGGUUCCCGCACCGGAUAGCAUGUUUUUGGCCCAGAGGAGCCUCUGCUCUCUUAGCGGUAGAGCAAAAUUCCUGAAGACAAUUUCUUCUUCCAAAAUCCUCGGAUUCUCUACUUCUGCUAAAAUGUCACUGAAAUUCACAAAUGCAAAACGGAUUGAAGGACUUGAUAGUAAUGUGUGGAUUGAAUUUACCAAAUUGGCUGCAGACCCUUCUGUUGUGAAUCUUGGCCAAGGCUUUCCAGAUAUAUCCCCUCCUACAUAUGUAAAAGAAGAAUUAUCAAAGAUUGCAGCAAUCGAUAGCCUGAAUCAGUAUACACGAGGCUUUGGCCAUCCAUCACUUGUGAAAGCUCUGUCCUAUCUGUAUGAAAAGCUUUAUCAAAAGCAAAUUGAUUCAAAUAAAGAAAUCCUUGUGACAGUAGGAGCAUAUGGAUCUCUUUUUAACACCAUUCAAGCAUUAAUUGAUGAGGGAGAUGAAUAUAAUGCAUGUACAGUAAAGUUCACAAAUCUUAAAUGUACAGCUGGAUAAAUUACUGUGUAAAUUUCUGUGCAACUACAACCAGACAAAGAUAUGAUACAUUUCCAGUACCCAGAAAACUUCUUUGUUCCUCUUCAGAGUCUAUAUUCUCCCAGAGGUCAUACUAAUAGUGCCUUUCUAUGACUGCUAUGAGCCCAUGGUGAGAAUGGCUGGAGCAACACCUGUUUUUAUUCCCCUGAGAUCUAAACCUGUUUAUGGAAAAAGAUGGUCUAGUUCUGACUGGACAUUAGAUCCUCAAGAACUGGAAAGUAAAUUUAAUUCCAAAACCAAAGCUAUUAUACUAAAUACUCCACAUAACCCACUUGGCAAGGUGUAUAACAGAGAGGAACUGCAAGUAAUUGCUGACCUUUGCAUCAAAUAUGACACACUCUGCAUCAGCGAUGAGGUUUAUGAAUGGCUUGUAUAUUCUGGAAAUAAGCACUUAAAAAUAGCUACUUUUCCAGGUAUGUGGGAGAGAACAAUAACAAUAGGAAGUGCUGGAAAGACUUUCAGUGUAACUGGCUGGAAGCUUGGCUGGUCCAUUGGUCCAAAUCAUUUGAUAAAACAUUUACAGACAGUUCAACAAAACACGAUUUAUACUUGUGCAACUCCUUUACAGGAAGCCUUGGCUCAAGCUUUCUGGAUUGACAUCAAGCGCAUGGAUGACCCAGAAUGUUACUUUAAUUCUUUGCCAAAAGAGUUAGAAGUAAAAAGAGAUCGGAUGGUACGUUUACUUGAAAGUGUUGGCCUAAAACCCAUAGUUCCUGAUGGAGGAUACUUCAUCAUCGCUGAUGUGUCUUUGCUAGAUCCAGACCUCUCUGAUAUGAAGAAUAAUGAGCCUUAUGACUAUAAGUUUGUGAAAUGGAUGACUAAACAUAAGAAACUAUCAGCCAUCCCCGUUUCAGCAUUCUGUAACUCAGAGACUAAAUCACAGUUUGAGAAGUUUGUGCGUUUUUGCUUCAUUAAAAAAGACAGCACACUGGAUGCUGCUGAAGAAAUCAUCAAGGCAUGGAGUGUACAGAAGUCUUGAUUUGUGCAGAAUGGAUUAAUGUUUCUGUUAGAUGACCUAGUAUGGAAUUGUUACUUAGUGCUGCCACCUGCUGGAUGUUAAAAGGUAUUUCAGUACAACUGGAAUUUAAAUAUUUCCAUUGUUUUUCCAAAGCAGUUAACCCAACUCCUAACAACAUUUUCGGGGGAUCUGACCUUUUUUUUCCAGUUGAAAUGUAUUAACACACCUUCCACAAUCAUUUUAUAAGAGUCAGCAUAACAUAGUGGAUAAGAAAUGUGAGAUGUUUAACCUCUCAGUAACUCGGUUCUCUCAUUAUAAAAUAGGAAUAAAAUCAGUACCUGUUUCAUAUGAAGGUCGUUUCUGAGAAUUAAAUGGACUAAUGUAUGCAAAAAGCCUGGCAAACAAUAAACACUCAUCUGACUUUAGCCGGU